ACUUCGCCGCCGGCCGACGGGCGCCAUUGUGCGGCGCGCGCCGGGUGAGUGCCGCGCGAAACCUGCGUCCGUCGGGGGCUGCGCUGGGCGGGUCCAGAACCGUUAGUUGGGGGCGAGCGCGGCCUCUGCAUUUUCCGCCGAGCUCGGGUACCCUGAGCCGGCCGUGCCUGCAGUCCUCCCGCCGCUCUGUGGGAUGGGGUCGGUGACCCGGAACCCCGAGGGGAGACAGUGCUUUCGGGGCGCCGCGGUGGAGAGAACAGAUCGCCUCCGGAAGCGUGGGGUCUGGGCCAGGGAGGCGAUCCCCUCCGAUGCGCGGGACAGAGGAGGCUCGGUGUCCUCUCGGGGAGGGGAAAACUGGUCCUAUCCAGUCCUGUGGGAGUCCUAUGACUCACUCUGGGCGUUUUCCAGUUUGGGUGGACUUGUCAUUUCCCGCUGAGGGAGCCGUUCCUGGGCGGAGGCUGCGGUAGCUCCCCAGCGGACACCUUAAGCCUCUCCCUCCCCUCCCAACUUCGGUUUCCUCAGGACUCUGCCCACUUCCACCAGAGACACAUUGAGAAGGAGGAAACUAUGGCCUCCAGGCUUCCGACGGCCUGGUCCUGUGAACCAGUGACCUUUGAAGAUGUAACACUGGGUUUUACCCCGGAAGAGUGGGGACUGCUGGACCUCAAACAGAAGUCCCUGUACAGGGAAGUGAUGCUGGAGAACUACAGGAACCUGGUCUCAGUGGAACAUCAGCUUUCCAAACCAGAUGUGGUAUCUCAGUUAGAGGAGGCAGAAGAUUUCUGGCCAGUGGAGAGAGGAAUUCCUCAAGACACCAUUCCAGAGUAUCCUGAGCUCCAGCUGGACCCUAAAUUGGAUCCUCUUCCUGCUGAGAGUCCCCUAAUGAACAUUGAGGUUGUUGAGGUCCUCACACUGAACCAGGAGGUGGCUGGUCCCCGGAAUGCCCAGAUCCAGGCCCUAUAUGCUGAAGAUGGAAGCCUGAGUGCAGAUGCCCCCAGUGAGCAGGUCCAACAGCAGGGCAAGCAUCCAGGUGACCCUGAGGCCGCGCGCCAGAGGUUCCGGCAGUUCCGUUAUAAGGACAUGACAGGUCCCCGGGAGGCCCUGGACCAGCUCCGAGAGCUGUGUCACCAGUGGCUACAGCCUAAGGCACGCUCCAAGGAGCAGAUCCUGGAGCUGCUGGUGCUGGAGCAGUUCCUAGGUGCACUGCCUGUGAAGCUCCGGACAUGGGUGGAAUCGCAGCACCCAGAGAACUGCCAAGAGGUGGUGGCCCUGGUAGAGGGUGUGACCUGGAUGUCUGAGGAGGAAGGAGCCAGUGACCUUCCAGGAUGUGGCUGUGGACUUCAGCCGGGAGGAGUGGGGGCUGCUGGGCCCGACACAGAGGACCGAGUACCGCGAUGUGAUGCUGGAGACCUUUGGGCACCUGGUCUCUGUGGGGUGGGAGACUACACUGGAAAAUAAAGAGUUAGCUCCAAAUUCUGACAUUCCUGAGGAAGAACCAGCCCCCAGCCUGAAAGUACAAGAAUCCUCAAGGGAUUGUGCCUUGUCCUCUACAUUAGAAGAUACCUUGCAGGGUGGGGUCCAGGAAGUCCAAGACACAGUGUUGAAGCAGAUGGAGUCUGCUCAGGAAAAAGACCUUCCUCAGAAGAAGCACUUUGACAACCGUGAGUCCCAGGCAAACAGUGGUGCUCUUGACACAAACCAAGUUUCGCUCCAGAAAAUUGACAACCCUGAGUCCCAGGCAAACAGUGGCGCUCUUGACACAAACCAAGUUUUGCUCCACAAAAUUCCUCCUAGAAAACGAUUGCGCAAACGUGACUCACAAGUUAAAAGUAUGAAACAUAAUUCACGUGUAAAAAUUCAUCAGAAGAGCUGUGAAAGGCAAAAGGCCAAGGAAGGCAAUGGUUGUAGGAAAACCUUCAGUCGGAGUACUAAACAGAUUACGUUUAUAAGAAUUCACAAGGGGAGCCAAGUUUGCCGAUGCAGUGAAUGUGGUAAAAUAUUCCGGAACCCAAGAUACUUUUCUGUGCAUAAGAAAAUCCAUACCGGAGAGAGGCCCUAUGUGUGUCAAGACUGUGGGAAAGGAUUUGUUCAGAGCUCUUCCCUCACACAGCAUCAGAGAGUUCAUUCUGGAGAGAGACCAUUUGAAUGUCAGGAGUGUGGGAGGACCUUCAAUGAUCGCUCAGCCAUCUCCCAGCACCUGAGGACUCACACUGGCGCUAAGCCCUACAAGUGUCAGGACUGUGGAAAAGCCUUCCGCCAGAGCUCCCACCUCAUCAGACAUCAGAGGACUCACACCGGGGAGCGCCCAUAUGCAUGCAACAAAUGUGGAAAGGCCUUCACCCAGAGCUCACACCUUAUUGGGCACCAGAGAACCCACAAUAGGACAAAGCGAAAGAAGAAACAGCCUACCUCAUAGCUCUCAAGCCAGUUGAAGAAACCUUGCCUUUUCAGCUUGACCCUGCAAUAUAACAUGCACAGGCCUGCUUGUGAAUCAGGACUGAAUGUGAAAGGGAAGUAUUGAGUGAGGACAUUCCCAAAACCAAAGGACAACUGAGGAGACUGCCCAGCACAUAAUGAAUAAAUAAGAAAAUGAGUGAGGAGUUAUUAACAUCAUUUGGAAAAAAGAUUUCCCAUUCACUUGAUAUUGUUUGUUCACUCAUUUAGUCAUUAAAAGUGAGAUUAAUAAAAUCUGAAAAUGUUAUAUAAUAACUUUAAAAAGCCAGGUAAUUAAUAAUCUGCACUGAUAUUACAUCCACAGUACCACAGUAUUUAUGUGUAUGAAUUAAGGAUUAAAAGAUAAUGUGGAUAAAUAAACUAUUGAUCUAUGUCUGUGUA